AGUUCUUUCCGGCUUCGCUGCUGGUGUCGGCUCCGAGAGCUCUGGCUUAUCAGGACUCCAUAGUUCUCCAACAGAGAAAUCUUGAAAAGGACUGACCAGUUUUUGCAGUUCUAAAACCAUGGCCCAUGGUUCAGUGACAUUCAGGGAUGUGGCCAUAGACUUCUCACAGGAAGAAUGGGAAUUCCUGGAUCCUGCUCAGAGGGACUUAUAUAGGGAUGUAAUGUGGGAGAACUACAGCAACUUCAUUUCACUAGCAGGACCUUCCAUUUCUAAACCAGAUGUGAUUACCUUAUUGGAUGAAGAAAGGAAGGAACCUGGGAUGGUUGUGAGGGAAGGGACAAGAAGAUACUGCCCUGAUUUGGAGUCCAGAUACAGGACCAAUACUUUAUCUCCAGAAAAGGACAUUUAUGAAAUAUAUUCAUUUCAGUGGGAUAUAAUGGAAAGAAUUAAAAGCUAUAGCCUUCAGGGUUCCAUUUUUAGGAAUGAUUGGGAAUGCAAAAGCAAGAUUGAGGGGGAAAAGGAACAACAAGAGGGAUAUUUUGGGCAAGUGAAAAUUACCUCUGAAAAAAUGACCACUUACAAAAGGCACAAUUUUCUUACUGAGUAUCAGAUCGUUCAUAAUGGAGAAAAGGUGUAUGAGUGUAAGGAGUGUAGGAAGACCUUUAUUCGUCGCUCAACACUUAGUCAACACCUGAGAAUUCAUACUGGUGAGAAACCUUAUAAGUGUAAGGAAUGUGGGCAGGCCUUUAGACAGCGUGCACAUCUUAUUCGACAUCACAAACUUCACACCGGUGAGAAACCCUAUGAAUGUAAGGAGUGUGGGAAGGCCUUUACAGUGCUCCAAGAACUUACUCAACAUCAGAGACUUCAUACGGGUGAAAAACCCUAUGAAUGUAAGGAAUGUGGAAAGGCCUUUAGAGUACAUCAGCAACUGGCUCGACAUCAGAGAAUUCACACUGGUGAGAAACCCUAUGAAUGUAAGGACUGUGGAAAGACCUUUAGACAGUGUACACACCUUACACGCCAUCAGAGACUUCAUACUGCUGAAAAGCUCUAUGAAUGUAAGGAAUGUGGGAAAGCCUUCGUAUGUGGUCCAGACCUUAGAGUACAUCAGAAAAUUCAUUUUGGUGAGAAACCCUAUGAAUGUAAGGAGUGUGGAAAGGCUUUUAGAAUAUGCCAACAACUUACUGUUCAUCAGAGUAUUCAUACUGGUGAGAAACCCUACGAAUGUAAGGAAUGUGGGAAGACUUUUAGAUUAAGACAACAACUAGUUCGCCAUCAGAGAAUACAUACUCGUGAGAAACCCUAUGAAUGUAUGGAAUGUUGGAAGACCUUUAGUAGUUACUCACAGCUUAUUUCACACCAGAGCAUUCAUAUUGGUGAGAGACCCUAUGAAUGUGAAGAGUGUGGAAAGGCCUUUAGACUGCUCUCACAACUUACUCAGCAUCAAAGUAUUCACACUGGUGAGAAACCUUAUGAAUGUAAGGAAUGUAGAAAACCUUUUAGACUGCUCUCACAACUUACCCAACAUCAGAGUAUUCACACUGGUGAGAAACCUUAUGAAUGUAAGGAAUGUGGUAAGGCUUUUAGACUUUAUUCAUUUCUUACUCAACACCAGAGAAUUCAUACUGGUGAGAAGCCCUACAAGUGUAAGGAGUGUAAGAAGGCCUUUAGACAGCAUUCACACCUUACUCAGCAUCAGAAGAUUCAUAAUGGAAUUUAAUAGAAGAAAGCCUUCAAAUGUAUAUGAUGUUACAGAACAUCAGAAAAUUCAUUUUUGAGAAAAUGUGUUUCAUGCUCAAUUCCAAGCAUAAUAAAUUUUAUAUUAGAGAAAGAAUAUGUUGAUUUAAAAGCCUUCCAACACCAUUUAAACAUGGUUUAUCUUCAGCAAAUUCCUAUGAGAGAAUAAUGUAAUGAAUGUAGGAAAAUCUUUAGCCUUAUCUGUCAUUAUCUCCCUUUCUCCACUUGAUUACCAGUUUGAUUUAUUGGACAAGAUACUAAGCUUCUGUGCCUCAUUUUGCUGACUUGUAAAAUGGUAAUAAUAGUACUUAUAUGUAUUAGUUAUUUAUUGCUGCGUAAUAAAUUACCACAGACUUAGUAGCAUAAAAUAACAUAUAAUUAUAUCUUAUAAUUUGGAUCAGGAGUAUAGGCAUGACUUAGUUGGGUCCUCUGCUUCAGGGUCUCUUGCAAGGCUACAGAUUUCAGCCAGGGCUGAGGUCUCAUCUGAAGGCUCAACUGGGGAAGGAUCCACAUCCAGACUAACAUAGUUGUUACCCAAUGUAUUUCCGUGAGGCCUGUUGCAUUGAGAUUCUCAGUUUCUAGCUGGCUGUUGGCUGAACGCUGACUGCAGCUCCUGGCCACAAUAGCCUCAUCAACAUGGCUGCUUGCUUCAUCAAGGCAUGCAAGCCAAAAGGGAGGACAGUCUGCUAGCAAGAUGGAAGUUACCAUCUUGUGUAAUCUAAUCAUGGAAGUAACAUUCCCUCACCUUCUACUGGUAGAAGUAAGUUACUAGGAUAGUCCACACUCAAGAGAACGGGAUGAUACAAGAGUGUGAAUAAGUCCUGGAGACAGGACCACUGGGGGGCCUGUUUAGAGUCAGCCUGCCACACUGUGGAAUAGGAUUGUUGCAAGGAGUAAGUAGUUAAUACUUGGAGGAAUCACAGUCAUAUAGCAUGUAUUCUGUAAAUAUUAUCUGUAAUUGUUAUUAUUGUCAUUAGUAUUAGUGAAUUCACGUAAAAGGAAGAUCUGUAGACAUAAUAAAUGUAGAAAUGCCUCCUGUCACCUCUCAGAAAUUAUUAAACAUAAUUUAUUCUAGGUAAAAUUUAGAUUGUAGUGAAUGUAGGAAGUUCUUCAGCACUUGAGCUGCAUUAGAAAUUUCAUGCCAAAAAUGAAUUUCAUGAAUGUGAGGUCACUAGUAAUACAGCUGUUGAAGAAUUAGAGGGAAAUAGGAAAUGAUUUUCCCAUAAUUCCAGAAAGCAAAAGGCUUACAAUCCCUGUUGUCUGACCACAGUUUAAAAUUAAUUAGAAACUAUCAAAAAUGUGGCUUAAAAGAAAUUAACCACCUAGGAAUUUAAUAUUGUUGUGUAUAUUUAUGUGUGUGUAUAAAACUCCUGUGGGAAAGAAACAAAACAUCAUUCUAUAAGUCAGUAUACUUUUGGAUGCUCAAAAUGCCAUAUCUUCAACCAGUAGGAGUUGUUUCAAGUUGAGUUUUUGAUGUGAUCCCACCAAUAAUUUGAUAGUUUACUUGAUUGUGGCUGCAUAAUUUGGUAACCUAUGAAAGAUGCUAGAGCACCAAUGUAUAAUUUUUUUGAGACAGGGUGUCACUUUGUCCCCCAGGCUGGAGUGCAGUGGUACAAGCACAGUUCACUGUACCCUGUUCCUCCUGGGCUCAAGUGAUUCUUCCACCUAAAUUUUUUUUUUUUUUUUAGAGAAAGGGUCUCACUAUGUUGCCCAGGCUGGUCUUGAACUUCUGGGCUCAAGUGAUCCUCCCUCCUUGGCCUCCAAAGGUGCUGGGGUUACAGGUAUGAGCCACCACACCCAGCCCAACUCAUUAUUCUUGAAAUCAAUAAAUCAGAGGAAAAAUUGUCAUUUAGUUUCCUUUUCCCAUGUGAACCAAAUUUCAGGGUCACCAGAAGUUCAUCAAAUUCAAAUGAAUUUGGCCUGGCACAGGGGUCACACCUGUAAUCCCAGCACUUUGGGAGGACAAGGUGGGUGGAUCACUUGAGGCCAGGAGUUUGAGACCAACCUGGUUAACAUGGUGAAACCCUGUCUGUACUAAAAAUACAAAAUUUAGCCAGGCAUGGUGGCACACACCUGUAGUCCCAGGCUGAGGUGGGAGGAUCACUUGAACCCAAGAGGCAGAGUUUGCAGUGAGCUGAGAUCGUGCCACUGCACUCCAGCCUGGGUGACAGAGUGAGACCCUGUCUCAAAAAAAAAAUUUGUUUUUUGAAUGGGUUUUUCUUUUUUGAAGAAGUCUAAUAAAUCUAGAAGGAAUUAGAGGAUUAGAAAAAUCACCAUUUUCUAGACCUUAAUGGAAUAAUGGGUCCAGAAAACAUGAUCUUCAAUGGGUACUACAACUAAUAGGUGAAAUAUUUUAUAGCGAGAUUUUUAUGGUGGAUCUAUCAAACUGGCCACCUCUGAACCCUUUGAUCUGUUUUAACCUUAAUAAAAAUGGGUCUAUCAGACAACACACUUCCUGACGUAAUGCAAUAGGAAGUCCACACCACCAUCUACAAAGCCUUAUUGCUGGAAUAAUGAACUGAAAGCAGACAGGGACUAGAUGAACAGUAUAUGGUCAUCCCUUGGUAUCCAUGGGGAAUUGGUUCCAGGAUCCUCCACUGAUGGUAAAAUCUGAGGAUGCUCAAGUCCCUUGUAUAAAAUGGCAUAGUAUGUAUUUGCAUAUUACCUACUCACAUCUUCCUGUAUACUUUAAAUUAUCUUUAGAUCACUUAUACCUAUCACAAUGUAAAUACUAUGUAAAUAGUUGUUAUACUGUAUUUUUCAAUUUGCAUUAUUUUUAUUGUAUUUUAUUUUUAUUGUUUUUUUUUGAGUAUUUUCUAUUUGAGAUUGGUUGAAUCUGCACAUAUGGAGGGCUGGCUAUAAAGGGCACCACAAGGAAGAAGCCAAACAGAUCCAGAAUGUGUGAAAUUCUACAGAGCAAAUUACCUGAUUUCUUCAACUAACAGGUAGCAUGAAAAUACAAGGGGAAGGGCAACCAUUAACAGAUUAAAAGAGACUUAAAGAGACAUAUCAACUAAAUUCAGUAUGUUGGCAUUACUUGGACCUGGUUUGAACAAAACAUAAAAAGCCAUUUUGGAGACAGUGAGGGAAGUGUGGACAUGGACUAAAUAUUAAAUGAUAUUUACAUAUAUUAAUUUGGUUAGGGAUUAUGUCAGUGUGAUUAUAAAAAAUAAAAGAUCGUAUGAUAUGAGAUACAUACUAUGAAAUGAAGAUAGACACAUUUGGAUUAAAAUAUUCUAGCAAAAGAAAUAAUUGGCAAAGAGAGCUGGAAACUAAAUUGGCAACAUGUUGAUAAUUUAAGUGGAGUGUUUUGUUCAUGGAGACUUAUUGUUCUAAUAUUUCUACUUUUGUAUGUGUUUGAAAUUUCAAUAAUAAAAUGUUUAAAAUCAAAACCAAAAUUAUAGACUAUGUAGAAAUGAAUGACAGUGAGAUGCCUGCACAUCUAACCUUGUCAGAUAUAAUCAAAGUUCUGUUCAGUGACAAAUUAAUGCCCUGUAAUGUGGUAAGGAAAUCUUAUUUGUGGAUACAGUCUUCAUCUUCUUCACUUACCCACAGCAGCAACACCAGGCCUGUCACACAGAUGAAUGUGUUGAGGGAAUGAAUAAGUAUUUCCGUCAAGAAAAAGGAAACAACAAAAUAAAACCAACCCAAGUAAAGAACAGCCAAGUGGCCAGGUGCGGUGGCUCAUGCCUGUAAUCCCAGCACUUUGGGAGGCCAUGGCAGGUGGAUCACCUGAGGUCGGGAUUUUGAGACCAGCCUGACCAACACUGAGAAACCCCAUCUCUAUUAAAGAUACAAAAUUAGCCAGGCAUGGUGGUGCAUGCCUGUAAUCCCAGCUACUUGGGAGGCUAAGGCAGGAGAAUCACUUGAAUCCAGGAGGCGGAGUUUGUGGUGAGUUGAGAUCGCGCCACUGCACUCCAGCCUGGGUAACAGAGCAAGAGUCUGUCAAAAAAAAAAAAAAAAAAAAAGGAACAGCCAAGUAACAGUAGAAAGUAGAAAUUAAGAGAAUGGAGAAUAUUAGACUUGAUUCAAUGUUAAUAGUGAUUAGAUUUUGGCAGUUAUAAUCAAGGAAGAGAAAAUGAAAGAUAAUACAUUUAGAGUAUUAAUGAUGAUAAAAGAGACACAACUCUAGAUUAUAUCAAGCAGAUUUUUAAAAUUAUAAGGCAAAACUAGGCCGGGCACAGUGGCUCACACCUGUAACCCCAGCACUUUGGGAGGCCGAGGUGGGUGGAUCACUUGAAGUCAGGAGUUCGAGACCAGCCUGACCAACAUAGCAAAACCCCAUCUCUACUAAAAAUACAAAAAUUAGCCUGUCAUGGUGGCGGGCACCUGUAAUCUAAGCUACUGGGGAGCCUGAGGCAGGAGAAUUGCUUGAACCCAGGAGGCAGAGGUUGCGGUGAACCAAGAUCACGCCACUGCACUCCAGCCUGGGUGACAGAGUGAGAACCUGUCUCAAAAAUAAUAAACAUAAUAUGGUAAAACUAUACAUGCACACAUGCACAAACGUGUAUAUUCAUUCCAGUACAAGUAAAAAUGUAGGAUUGCAUUUUUCCCCCAAAAGGAAUAUGUUUUACAAUUAACUCACCGUAUAACCCAAAUAGAUUAACAAAAAAUGUGUGUGUGUGUGUGUGUGUGUGAACUCCCUGUUUAAAAAAUCUGAUACUUAUAAAAACUUUAAGGAAUAGAUAAUCCUAAAGAUUUUACCAAUUAAUUCUGCAAGGUAAAAUAAUCCUAAUAAAAAUUAGAUGAAGAUAGUUUCUGAAAGCAAAUUCUAGACCACCUUCAUUAUGAAGAUUCUAUUUUUCACAAUUCUAAAUAAAGUUUAUUUAGAAUUUAUUACAAAAUCUAUCUUUGCUAAUAGGUCAGUGUUUCUUUUCCCAAGCACCAAAUACCUCCAGAAAGCCUGUGUUUGACCCCUAAAUUCAACAUUCUCCAGAAGUUUGCUUCAAGGAAUAUUAAUUCUCGAUGGUAUUUGAAAAAAAGAUUUCUUGGGAAAAUAGGCAAAUGAAGCAAAACAUAAAACAUCUACUUUUGGCCAGGCACGGUGGCUCACGCCUGUAAUCCCAACAUUUUGGGAGGCCAAGGCGAGCAGAUCACUUGAGGUCAGGAGUUUGAGACCAGCCUGGCCAACAUGGUGAAACCCUGUCUCUACUAAAAAUACAAAAUUAGCUGGGCGUGGUGGCUUGCACCUGUAAUCCCAGCUACUUGGGAGGCUGAGGCAGGAGAAUUGCUUGAACCCAGGAAAUGGAGAUUGCAGUGAGCUGAGAUUUUGCCAUUGCACUCCAACCUGGGCAACAAGAGUGAAACUCAGUCUCAAAUAAAAUAAAAUAAAAAUCUACUUUUGAGGAAUUCAAAGUAUACAUGAUCAGUUUGCCAAAGAUUUAGUAAAGACAUUUUUAUUUAACUGAGUGUAUCUCAAAUUUAUUGUGGAAUUCUCAGUCCGAAUAUCUGGAAUAGGAACAGCUUUGUUAGAUGCUACCAUAACCACAAUGAAUGUCUUCAAGGGUGUAAUUUUAGAUAUGGUGAGUGGUUGUGUUGGGGGCGGCAUAAGUCAGGGCAAUUUUUUGCAGCUCAUAUCAUGCUCUGAAAGUAGCUACCUGCUUUAAUGGAUGGUUAGUGCUUUUCUAUAGAAUGGAAAAGAUUCCAGCCCGAUCCUUGAUAUGUUUGUGUUAAACAUGCUUAUAUAUUAUAUUAAACAAUGAUUAAGGACAUAAAUGAGUUUCUGUGGUAAUAAAGAUGCUAUAUUGAAUAUCA